AUUCUCCGCGGCGCGGCGGCGAGUGCUGGCUGCGGUACCCUCCCGCUCGCUUGUCCGUCUGCGCGCCCGCGAUGUGACCAGCCGACUGGGGGCGGGCUGGCGGCUCUGCCUGCGGCAGCGCAUCGGUUUUUCUCCUGGCAGGUCCCUAAUUGAGCCGUGAUUCCCUUGGAGCCAGAGACACCCACCAGGGGCUCGGAGCGCCGCGCUCCGGGGCUGGAGGCAGCUGCAGCGCUCGGGUCCGCGCGGCCGGGUGCAGUAGCCUCAGUCCCAGCCGCCGCCUCGCUGAGUCGUGUGCCCUGGCGAAUGCCCGGCGCCCGGCACAGCUGAGCCAAGGCGACUGGUGCAGAGCGGCGGCGCCUGGUCCUGCACUUGCCGCUGCUGCCGGGCUGUGCCGGGGCGGCGGCGCUGCGCGCCGGAGUUUGCAGAGGCUGCCUCCGAGCGCCGUCCGCCAGGAAGACUCCCUGCCUCCUGAGUCCCAGUAAGUUGACUGUAGUUUCUGAAGUUGGAGGGAGCCGUGGGAAGGAGAGGUUCGUUUUUAUCUUCUUGUGGGAAGCCGAGGGUGGCACCUCUUGUUAACAGAGUUCCAGCUCGAGGAGGGAGUGCGGGGUGCCAAGAAGGGGACAAGGCAGCUGGAAGGUCUGGAGUCCAGGGCUGGCUGACCUCAGCAUCUCACGAAUGUGCCAGUUGGAAAUAUGCUGGGAGAGGACAGGUACUCCUAGGGCAUUUCGACUGCUGCGUGCUAAUUAUUCAUUCCAAGCUCCUUGACUCUGUGUUUACGUUGGGGUGAAGGGGCUGGGCAGGGUCUUGUCACCUCCAUCCUAAUUCCUCUGGGGAGUGUGGCCAGCACUGCGAUGGAUCUUUGGGCGAGCCAUUUCUUUCAGGCCUGCAGGCUUCCCGCGCAUCCCGCUUUACUCUUCCCCUAGGCAGAAGUUGCCAACCUUUUCAUAAUUGGAGCCUAGUCCUUUAGGGAAAAAACAACUUAUAUGUCGACCCGGUGUUUUAUGCCCUAAGGCAAAUAAAACGAGCUCUGGGCGUGUGAAUUCAUACACUUUAAGAAUGUAGGCAAGUCUCAAGAAAUAGGAUUCAGAUAAUGACACUUGGAUUUCACCCUGAUUGUCCUGCACCUCUUAUGUAAGCCUCCCGGCUGGAUAACUUUAUCUCUGCAGUGGCUGCAGCUGUGGCCCUCCAUUCCAUUUGUUUAAAGUCCAAUUGAACAGUAUUUACUGAAAAUGCUGACAUGAUAUAGCGGCCUGAAGUCUGAAACAGAGUGCACUCUUCAAAUUGGAGUGUCUUCUCCUAAUAGGGAGCAUGGGAGGAACAACCCACUAUAUUUUUCAAGGCAGCUCCAGGAAUUAGACCCAUAAAUCAUGUUUUAAAAUAGCAUGCAUUGUGCAGAGAGCAUGCAGAGGACCGCUUUUUGAACACAUCCCCUUUGUUUUAGAAAAAGUGGAAAUUGUUCAUGCCAGACAAUUGUUGAGUCUAAAAGUUAAGUGUACUGAUGGGCCUAAUUAUCUUAAUAAACAAAGAGCAUGAUUUAUAGGUAGCUGCAGUGCCCUACUUUGAAGGAUAGAAAUCUUUAACCUUUCUUUCUCAGCUGUUCCCGAGAGAUUCCUUUUAAGCAGAGCUAUGGAUUAUCAUCAUUGAUGUUUAAUACCUGAGUUGGUUAAACUUGUAAAAGGAAUAGUACUUUGAAGUACCAUGCAGUACUGCUGUGUGACUGUUACACAGCGAAUAUUAUAAAUAAGAGGAAUAUUUGGAGUAUUGGGUAUAGAUGUCAUUAGUUUAACAAAAUAGGUCAUAUUAAGACUUUCCUGCUAAAUAUAUAUACACAUACAUAAAUGUUUAAUUUGGACUUGAAAUUAUUGUUUAAACCAAAGCUCAGGGGUAUGUUUUAAUGUAAGAUUUAUUUACAUAAUCUUUGAAGAGAGAAGUGCAUUUAUUUAUGGUAUUUCAGCAUGCAGAACAAGAUGAACUAGUUAUAGGCACCUUAUUUAAAGUGUAAAGGGUUUUUUUUUAGGAAUACUAAGAAAAUACACAAAAUGUUAUUUCAGAAGUUGAAAAGUUAGUCACAUCAACACAUUGCGGUUUGUGAGAGCAUCCAGUGCUUAUCUCUAGAAGAGAUUACAUCCAAGCAUGGAAUCUCAAACAGAUUGACCCAUUAAGCCCUAUUGCAGCCUGGUUAGGAGGACAGGCUAUGGAGCCAGGCUGCCAGCUCUGGUACCAUCUGUUUGAAUCUAGGCAAGUAACCCAAAGUCUGUGCCUCAGUGUCUUCAUCUGUACAAUGGGGAUGACAGUAGUAGUACCUACCCCACUGAACAGUAGUGAGAAUUAAAUGAGUUCAUAGACAUAGAGCUGUUGGGCCAGUAUCUGGCAUAUUAAGCUUGUUCUGGGAAAAAUUUUCAUUGUUAUGAAAGGAAAUGCAUCUUUGGACUCUAUGGACAUUGAAUUGCUGCUAUGGACAUUGAAUUGCUGCUGAUGAAUAUUAACAGAAGCAGUUCAUGUGUAUAAUAGGAGAGAAGGUAUAAACAUUUAUUGUGCACUGUCUAGCGAUACAGACACCAACUGGUAUUUAACACUGUCUUGCUCAAUUCCCCACCACAGUCCUUUGAGGUAAGUGGCUUCAUCUCUACUUUAGAGAUGAGAAAAUGGGAGCUCAGUGAGAUCAAAUAGUAGAAAUUGGAGCUGGCAUUUAACCCACGUCUGUCUGUGUUGAAACUGUGUUCUUUUUGACCCUGCUGCCUCAACUUGCAAAUGAAGUAGUUGCAUUAUUAUCCUCAAUUUAUACAUGAAGAAAUCUAAGCUUAAGGAUUAAAGUAUGCAAAGUGCUUAACAGCACCCACAACAGAAAUGAUCAUAAUUAUUGUUAAAUAACUUGCCCAUGCUUCCAUACCUCCUAAUGUGUGGUAGAGGUGCCAGGUCUUUCAAUUUGAAGUGGAUUCUGUUGCUUUAUUAUUUUUCUAUUCAUGCAUUCAGAGAGUCAAAAAAGAAAAAUUGGUGUGAUGUUAGAGUUUACACUGGAGGGUGGUGGUCUCCAUUUGGUUUCCUGCCUGCACGUGUAGCUGCAGCAAUCUACACAGUCAAGGAAACCACCACGGCAGCAGUAAUCAAUCCACAAACAGCGUCAUCCCUGGAUAUGCAUUCAGUCCCAGCUGGAGAACUCCCUUGGGCAGAGAGAGGCCUUGCACUUUGCCUCAUAUUAAACUGCAUGUUCAGAAAAAGAAAUAAUUUAUACUUACCAUUAAAUAAGCAUGCUUCCUUCAAGCCUUAGUACCCCAUGUCAUGGGAAGCAGAUUCCGGGGUGCUGUGUGAGCAGUACUUCCUUUAAGGUUUCCAUAGCUUGUUAGACUUCUCAGCUGGGUUCCAGAGGUGGGGAAUGAUUGAGAGGUCAUGGCAUUUUUGUGGCUGUGUUAGGUUAUCACCCAAAUACUAGAUAGUGUUCUCGCCUUUUGUAAGUCUUAUUUCUAGAGAUUAAAAUCUAAUUGCCGUAUAGGGCACAUAGACCACAGACUGCUCACAGUCUGAUUUAAUUUAAAUCACAGACUGAUUUAAUGUUUAAUGAAAUCUCUUAGCUAAUGUAUGCUAACACUGAAUGGUGCUUCAAUAUAAAUGCUCAAAGUUGGCUUUAAAAAAAAAAUCAAAACUCUUCGAGAGUUCUACUCUUCCUGUAGGCUGCCUCCAUGUGCCUGGGGACACAAUACCAUAGUUGCAAAGUGCCCAAAAGAGCCCCUGCCAUUGACUGAGUCAUCUCACAUCUCUGAAUUAUCUUCUGUUUCAACUUGAACCCUCCUUUUCAGAGAACAGAUAUUCCCUUUUGCUUACUUAAUAGUUAAUUUCAAGUGUUCCCCUGCUCUGGGUUGGUUAUUCUAUAGUAAAAGUCUCCCCUGAUCACUUUUGUGACUUGAAUGAGGUUCAUGAUUUAUUAUUAACUAACUCCUCAGAAUAUACAUAUAGUUGUUUCAUUUCUCAUCUAUGUUAUCUGUUAUCUAUUUAGUGGCUUAUCUGUGUCACUUUUAAAUCUCUGAAUAAUUUUCUUCUGACAUCCAUCAAAAGAUACAUGUAAAAGAAAUGCAAACUAAUUUUAAUAUGGAUAUAAAUGAAUGAAGACCAUUGACAGUCAUAUGUACUGUUUUGAAUUUUCUUCACUUUGGGCUUGAGGAGUUGGGAGCUGAUAGUUCCAGAGCUCCUGCCUCAUGCAUUGUGAGAGGCACAUUGGGAGGUUAUACAAGUUAUACACGCAAGCAGUUCAUGUGCAGCCCCGCAGAGACAGCCCCUGAGGGCUCGCUCAUUGCUGAGUUCAAGGGCAGGGGUUAAGUAUGAGGGGAAAACAGCUCUGUACAUAAUUUAUAUGACCACAUUUCUAGUCCUUACUGGUUAUCUUUCUGGAUAAGAAUUGGAAUGAAUAGCUUAAAGGGAGCACUUACUGUGUGUUGGCUGCCAUGUUAAGAACUGCCCUUCAUCCUCACUGUGACCUUGUGUGGUAGUACUUUAUUAUCCUCUUUUGUGGAAGUGACAACUGAGGCCUAGAAAAGUCAGGGCACUUGUCCACGGUGACACUAGUGAGCUUCAGAGUAAAGAGUGGAGCCCAGAACUGUGCAAGGAGGCCCGUGAUACUUAUAGAACGUUCUGCUGCCACUGAUUUUUGAGCCUUUGUGAUAGCUAAACUCUAUUGCAUGGAUUUAUAUAUUACAUAAUAUAGAUGGACUAUAUUAUGCUUUUCAGAAGAAUCCUAUACUAUCUUGCUUGGUCCCCAGGUGAAGGAAUGGUGGGAAGACACAUGCCUACCUUCUUAGCCACUGCCAGGAGCAGGAAUUGACAGCACAGGAAAUAUCAUCUCCAUUAUCUUUGUAGAAGAAGAGCUUAAGCUUAGUUCACGCAAUGAGCUCAAAAAAGAAAACCACAUGUCUGCUUUGUGAAAUAGGAAGCAUAAAGCCUUCAACUGGUAGUAGAGCACAGUGGGGAGGCAUGUUAACUUUAUCUGUGUUUAGUGUCACAUACUUGCAUCAUUCUCACUAAAAAAAAAGGAGAAGUGUGGAGACCUGACAUUUUCUUGGGUGAUUUAAAAGAAAAAUAAGUUUAUUUAAAUCUAAAGAAGUAUCAGCAGUGAACUGUCAUGGGAGAACCACAUUACUACAGCAGUGUCAUCUGUCAUCCCAUGAGACUAUGGUUUUCAAAGGAAACGAACACUUAUGUCUAACCAGUAAGGCUUAAACGUGUUAUCUUAUAGUAAGAACAUUGCAUCAAAUCGUCCAUGUCUGUAUCAUAGCCUUUCUAACUCCAGUCAAAAUGGAGGGUAAAAGGACAAUUUUAAAACCAUCUCGUAAUAUUUUCAAAACCCUUCCCCUGAGCCCUGCCCCCUCUAUUUUUUCUCGAUUUCAUACUGGUGCCAAUAUUUGUUCAAUAAGUUAAUUCAUAUCAUCCCCUGGAGUUUGAAUUAUAAAGGAAUUAUUGUGAUUAUAAUAUUUUGGCAUAUCCUGUUGAUCUCUCAUUUGCCCCCAUCCUUGAUGUUAUAGGACUGUAUGAUUUUUUUAACCUGAGAAGUGAUUAAAAACGUUUUAAAAAUUUAGUCUCCUAAAUGUAGACUGUUUAUUGCAGAAGACAGGGAAAUUGGCCUGACUGGGGGCAUUUGCUAAAAAUGCAGAGCUCCUGAAAUCCUGUGAACCUUAUGGAGUAAGCAAGUAAAAAAAAAAAUACGGAAGAAGAAGUAGUUUUAAAAUUGCUCACUAGGCCUGGUGCGGUGACUCACGCCUGUAAUCUGAGCACUUUGGGAGGCUGAGGAGGGUGGAUCACUUGAGGUCAGGGGUUCGAGACCAGCCUGGCCAACAUGGUGAAACCCAGUUUCUACUAAAAAUACAAAAAUUAGCUGGGCAUGGUGGUGUGCACCUGUAAUCCAAGCUACUCGGAAGGCUGAGGCAGGAGAAUCACCUGAACCCGGGAGGCAAAGGUUGAAGUGAGCCAGGAAGAUCACACCACUGCACCCCGGCCUGGGCAACAGAGUAAGACUUUGUCUCAGAAUAAAUAAAUAAAAAUAAAAUUGGUCACUAACAGCUUUGUACUUCCCUCUCCCAUUUCACAGAUGUCCAGCUGACCCAAUCCCUAGGUACCGUAUCAUGUAUUCAUUUGCAAGUAAUCAGGUUCUCUUGAUUUUCUAAAAGUACCAAAAGGUGUGACUAAAUCAGCAUUACUGUCAUCUGCCAUCUCCGUGUUGAGAGAGCCCCAGGGUUGCAUAUGUAAGCUUUUAUGUGAAUUUAUUCUCUGAGGAAUGAAGGGUGAUCAGAUAAGUUCUCAGGCAUCUCGUCUCACUGUAUUUGUGACUCCAUCAUUACUAUUAAAGUUGCUUCCCCCUACGCCAUCCUUUCACCCCAAACCAUACCCAUUCCUUCAUCAUGCCCAUUGUGGUGGAACAUGAUGAAACUAUUGGGAAACUUAAGUGUUGAGGGAGCUCAUGUUCUAAGUCAAAGGAAAAAACACAUAACACAAUACUUUUUUUCUUUUCAUUAAAAAAAAGCCAGUCCCUAACAUAGCUAUACACAAGAACACCACACCUUCUGCAUUCAGCAGUUGGGAAUUGCAACCAGAGUGGCCUUAUUAAUUUUUUCCUGGCACCUUCUAAGGAGGGCUGUGAGCCUCUAAUUCACAUGUAAUCAAUCACUAGCAGCUUGUCUGUGUUUUCAGUCAAAUUUAGUGACUGAAGGGUCACUAAAUAUCACAAGGGUGGUAUUUAUUCAUUUAUACAUUCACCAGAUAUAUAUUAAUAUGAUACCAGGCACAUUGUUAGAUGAUAAGACCUCAAAUACCAGAAAAUCCCUCUCUCUGCCCUCAAGAAUCUCAGAUUCAUGAGGGAAGGAGACACUGAGCAGCAGUUGGAACCAGUGCUUAAAGGAUGCUUGGCUCCGUCAGGGGUGCCUGACUCCAAGGGGAUGACUUUUCCUAACGCAGCCGGGCUUGAUGGAGUCUGGAAGAGCCAGUAGGAGGGUACCAGGAGGCUAAGGGUGGGAGUGGGCAGGGAGAAAUUAUUCUGAGAGAGGGAACAGGGAAUAUGGUGAAACAAAGGUACCGGAGAGGCGGGUUGUGGAACAGCUGGUCAUUCCAUGUGGCUGGUGCACAUUGAGGGUGGGGAGUGAGACUGGAGAUGGAGAGCGGAGGCUGGAGCCACUUUUGGAGGGUCUUGUGGGCCAUAUUUAGUUUUGUAGAUGAAUUUGAGUACUUUUUUAGAAUGAUCACUCUGGGUAUAUUACACAGAAUGGAUGGGGUAAGGGACAGACAAAGUAAGCUGUGCAAAAAAAGCUUUUGAAUACUGGUGUGGAUUUAAAGUCUAAACUCCCACUGAUAAGCGUGGGGACAUUAAGGGGAGAAGCAAGGAGAGGAUGGUGAAUUUAAGGAUGACUCCCAGGUGUCUGGCUUGGGAAUUGAAUCCAUAAGGCUGCCAUUGGAGAUGAUAAUGAAUACAGAGGAUGGAGCAGUUUGCAGGAGAAGAUGACAGGUUGUGGAUUUAUGCACUGUGAGGCACCAGAGGGACAUUCAGGACCUGAGAUGCAAUUGGCAGUUGUACAGCCUGUGGUUCUGGAAUUCAAAACGGAGGCCGAACUGGAAAUGCAGGUUUGCAAGUCUUCCGUGUAUUUGAAAUUGUUGUUGAGGUUGUGAUCUGCCUGUGAGAACGUGUGGACUGAAAAAAAAAAAAAAAAGGACGAAGGCCAAGGUGGCUGUCAGAAGAAAAAGAGAUGGCAUAGUAAGAUUAAGCAAGAGAAGUUUUUGACAAGUGCUUGGACACAAAGUGGCAGAAGCCAGAGGCAAAGCAGAAUGAGAUGCUUGAUUGAAUGGGAACUGAGUGACAAAAGAAAUGAAAUUGAAAUAAAAAGAGAGCAAAGGGACAGGUCUGACUGUUAACUUGCUUCCAUCUACACAGAUAAUGGUGGCUUUUACUCCUAGAGUUUCCGGUUCUGGUCAAUAAAUAUUAAGACCUACCAUGUGGAAGGUGGGUGGGAAAGGGGAUGGGGGGAAGAAAUAAAAUAACAAGGCAUGAAUUUCGAUCUCAAGAAGCGCAUGGAAUUUUCAUUUCUUAUUUUUUUCUGGAUCUCAAGAAGCUUAUAGAAUUAUCAUUUCUUAUUUUUCUUUUCCAUUUGUUUUUCUCCUUCAUUGACAGCAGGACACAGGCUUCAUGGGAGAAUGGAAAGAAUGAAAGAAUCAUUUUGUUGGUGCAUGAAGUGCCUCAGUUCCCCAUAGCGGGCAUAUCUCAUUUUAUCCACAAAAUAAACACACUGAAAGAGAAGGUGAUAAAUGAUCCAUUAUUUGACGGAUUGUAAAAACUAAGCUUUUAUCAUGGCCAUAAUGUUAUUAGAGGGUUUGGACCUUUGAGCCAAUGCUUAUGUAAUUAUUAAUGAGACUUUCGGCUCACUGGAUUAUUUGAUGUAUGCUGAGUAAAAUAUCCUAUAAUUUUCACUUGUCUUAUAAAAACAGGACACAUUAUAUUAUAGACUAACUGGAGUAUUUGGAGAUGAUGGAAAUAAUUACCGUAUGUUUUAGUUAAAUAUUAUGCCUUUCAGUCCUCAAACGUUUGUCCUUUAAUUUUGACCUAAAGGUAGAAUCACUCCCGUUAUACAUAUGAGGAAACUGAGAUACAGGGUUCAGAUGGGUGGGUGGAGAUAACACAGCUAGUAAGUGGUAGAGCUUCUAGGAUCCAAAAUGAGGUGUCCUGGGUUCGUACCACUCCAUCAUGUUGCUGUAUCUUUGUGAAUAGCUACUAAAGAAGAAUUAGGGGGUGUUAUGUUUAAGAGAUUUUCUUUAUUAGUCUGCUCAAAGCACCAACAGUAGAAGCUGUAUCAGCUACAAUUUCUAUAUUUGAUGGGCCACAGGUUAUUUAUGCAAAUAUAUGUGAUUAAGUUAGAUUGGGGGAAAAUCUGCUUUUUUUUUUUUUUUUCCCACAAAAUGAACAUGUUUUGCAUUCAUUAUCUCAAGAGCACUAAAAAAGAAUCUGAGUAUAAAUAUAAGGAUUCAAUAUUUUAACUUAUAAAAUUAUUGUAGAUAAACUUAUUUGUGAUACAGUGGGAAUUUAUUUUUCAGCAAUUGCAAUGGCUGUUGUCUGUAAGAGGCAUUCCGUGUGUACACGUACCUGUGUGUGCAUGUAUAAAAAAUAAAAUUUAGCCUAAUUAAUUUUAAACUAUUGGUUUUCCUUUUGUAAUAUUUUUGAAUUCUCCAGAUACAUUAAAUGAUAUUGCUUGCUUUGUCUUGCCAAAGCAGCUAUUAUGUUACUCAUUUAAUGCCAAAGUGUUAAAGCAUUUGUCUUCGGUAAGCAAUGUAAAAUGAUGUAGGAUGAGCCUAAGGGAUUUAGUUUAAUGUUACAACUUGUAUUUUGGCUCCUGAUAGUCUAAAUUUUUUAUUUACCUAAUUUUGCUACUAUUGAAGCAGAUAUUAGCUGUUAAUAUACAGUAAUAUUAGAAUCAUGAAAAGUACAUAGAAUGUUGUGGCUGGUGGAAAAACUUUAUGAUGCUGCAUUUUUUUCUUUCACAAAAAAUAUCUAGGAGGCUUACUAAAUUGCAAUUUCCAGAUGAAAGCAAUUUCUAGCAAGUAGCAAAAUGCUGGUGCUAAUGCUUAUCCCUAAAUCUCAAUUUCAAGCUUCAUGGUGCCUAUUUUACAUUUUAGCUUUGGUAGGAAAAGUUGAAUCCAAAGGGGCUUAUGCCUUUGUGACAUUUGGUGGAUUGCUCUUUUGUUAUUGGUGCUGAUUUUUAAAAAUAACAAUACAUUUAUAAAUUUUAAAAAGUUUUAAAAAACGUUAGGCAGCUAUCUUAGUUCUGAAUUAUCACUACACAUGGUGCAUUGUAGUAGCCUUAGUCCAAUGUAGUUGAAAAAUUACAAUAUAGGCAUGUGAAAAUUUAAAUAACAAUACAAAGUAAUAUGGUAUUUUAUAUUUGAUUUUUAUUGCACUUUAUAAUAAUAUGUGAGGAAACUCAAAUGAGGUAAAAUGAAGAUUAAUUUGGUCAUUUCAUGCCUCAUGUAUCCCAAUUUCAUCCAAAUGCAAAUAUGAUAAUCCAGGGCAUAGAGUUAGUGUUCUGUUCAGGUGAUUUGACACUACUGUAUUUAUUAAUCACUUCCAAGAUGAACAAUUAAACUGCAUUUCGUACUCAUCUUUCUAUGAGUAUAUAUUUUAAUAUUAUGUACUAGGAGUUUUCAUUUUCUAAAAAGUAAUUAAAUUUUCUUUGUCUUAUUUUUCUUAUUCUUAUUGAAUUUUAUUCAGACAUUUUUAUGUUAGUGUAUACUUGACAUGAUAGAACAUGUCUAAAUUAGUAAUCUAAUUUGAAUACCAUAAUUAUGUGUACAGUUAGAGCUUGAUUGAAUGGAGAGCUUUUGCACAUCCUGUAUGUUCUUUCUGUUAGUGGAUUUAGGAAUUACAUGCUUAAUACUAAAGAGUCCAAAGCCUGUUUAUGUUUAUCAGUAGGCGCACAGAGCAAAAUAUAAAUAUUUUUGCCAAUAGAAUUGGAAAAGAUAUGCUUCCUUUUUUAAGUGUUAGGAAUUAACACGUAACUGUCUGUGGUAGUUUUCUCUUAUACGAACAGAUUGAUAAGAAAUAUAGACAUGGCUGAAAACUAGAAUGGUGUCAUUGUAUUGCCUAAAUUGUUGGUGUUGAGGUUAGAAGUCCACUCCUUUGUUUUGCUAAAUAAGAAAUAAAGAUGCUUUAAAAUAUUGAUCAUAAGUCCUGAUAAAUAUUUGUACAUAUUUAGUGUUACGAAUAUUUUUCUUUUGCUUUAUUAUGUAGUGGUCACUUUGCCCAAAAUGUACAUCUUGACCUUUAGUAUGGAAUGCUCAGUAUGUCCGAGGUAGAAUUGAAACCAAAACAUCUGGAGUCUUAUUAAAAGGAUACAAUAUGGAUAACAGCUUUUUAGUCUUGGGGCUGAGAUAUUUGGAAGAGGAUUGCUAAAUACUGUGGUCAUUGAGAAAAAUAACACUGAUGUACUAAACUUACACUUAAUUUAAUGGUUUCGCUACCACCAUUCUUAACCUUUCCAACUGGCUGAGUUAUUUGCUAAUAGUGGCAUGUCACAUCCUGAAUUAUAGAUCUUUCCUUUUAAUAAAUAUUCAAUAGCAUUUUCAAAAUCGUUCUCCUAGAUACAAUUCAUAAUGAACAGCGCAGCGCUGGCAACAAGCAUGCUUCUUUCAGCCUGUUUUAUAGCCACAGGCUAUUUGGCAUUUGGACACUUCUCUUAUGUAUUUCCACAGCUCCACAUUUCCUAAAAACUGUCAGCCUUAUAUUAGAAUUAGCUUUUGCUUCUCCACAGUUACAUGGAGAAUGAAAAGAAUAUCUCUCCUUUUCUCUCCCUGUAAUAUGCCAAGGACUGUGGUCAGAGAAUCAUCAUUUGCUAGUCGUAUGCUUUUUCUUUCUUGAUGUUCUCAUUAGCUUCAGAAGCCAUAGCAUGAAAGGCAUUUUGAAAUGCGUCCGCCAUCGGUUUGGUUUGAUCCAUGUUAAACUUUUUCUGUCUAGAACUGUGGUUCUUAACCCCCUAGAGGACAUUUGGCAAUGUCUGAAGACAUUUUUGGUUGGCACAGCUGGGGAUGGGGAUGCUACUGGCAUCUGGUGGGUAGAGGCCAGGGAUGCUGCUAUACAUUCCACAAUGCACAAAAUAGCCCUCCCCAGGGAAGAAUUUUCUACCUCAAAAUGUCUAGAGUGCUAAGCUUGAGAAACCCUGAUUUAGAAGGUAGGGGAUGUCUGUUUAAUUUGUAUUAUAUUUUUUACGCAAACGAAAAGUGAUAGUUCUGGUGAAGAAAUCAUUGCAUAUAAUGUAAUCAUUUAUUGAACACCUACUAGGCUCUGAGAAUACAAUGAAGACUAUGACAUGGUUCUUGCCUCAGGGGUAUACCCUGUCUUUGCCAAAAUGAUUAGUAAAUAAAAUCAAACUGGUUGAUGUGAUGUAUGCUGUGAUUAGAGGUAUGCAUGGCAUGUUAAGAUAAAAAUAAUUUAGAUUUCAUUUGCUAAAUAUAAGAGAAUAUCUGGAAGGGAUUGUUCUCUGACUAAAUGUAAUAUCAGUCAUUUGUGGGUAAAGAAUUUCUAAUUUUUCCUUGACAAUUAGGAGUAAGUUUUAUUUAUUGUCUUUUUAAAUUUCAACUGGCAUUACUGUGAAAUGUCAGGAAAGAAGGGAAGGUGUUGACAUAAAAAGUGUUACUUCAGGAAUUUAGGAAAUGAGUUUUUCAUCAUCUUCAUCGAGUUCUAGUUUACAUGCCAUAAAAGUCUCCAAUUUCAACUGAACAAUUCACUGAUUUUUAGUAAACGUACAGAGCUAGGGAACUGUCACCACAAUUCAGCUUUAGGACUUUUCUAUCACCCCAAAAAGCUCCCUUGUGCCUGUGUGCAGUUCUCAUUCCUGCUGCCAGCCCCAGGAAGCCACCAAUCUUUCUAUUGCUUGCUUUCUUUUCUGUCUCACUUUCUGUCCUUAUAUAUUUGCCUUUUAGCAAAUCUCUGGACAUUUCAUUUGAGAUAUUAAUAUUUACCAAUAAAAAUGUAGUUUCUAUCUUCUUUUUCAAGAUCAGCAUCACCUUAUUUUUUUUAUAUUGCCUGUACCAUACACAUGCUACAGUGCAGGUUCAGGGACUCUUAGUUAUCGGAACUCUCAGACUAAUAAAGUGAAACAUGCAGCAAAGAAGUAAAGCACAUGUGUAAGAGUGGAAUGUGUGCCUGUUUCUCAGCUUUGUCCCUGUUUCAAUGGUGGUCACCCCCUCUACUACUUUUGUAACUCUGUCUACAAAAAUAAUGUUAUAGAAAGCAUUGAAAAGCUGAAGUCAGAUAAAUACUCUCAAGAUGUGGGGAAACUACAAAAGGAUUAAAUCUGGAGAACAUGCCUGUUUGGGAGCUGUAUUCUGGUCAACCAUUUCUUAGCCAAACCCUUUGGGGCCAAAUGUCUUUCAGAAUUCAGCUUUUAGAAAGGUAAUACAGUGUAUUCAUUGUAUAUUAAUGUAAUACCCCCAUGGGAUCCAGGCAACACACAGUAAUUUUUGUAGCAAAGUAGAUGAAUAUUCACAUUUAGUUAGAGAAAAACUAACCACAUGUCAGUUCAGGUCAGUUUGGGGAACAAACUCAUUUCGUAGCAAAAUAACAAACUCUGUUUUCAGAAAUUUUUGCAUUUCAAAAUUGUGGGUAAAGGUUUGUGAGACUGCCUCAGUGUAUCCCAGGAUAUUGCAUUUCAAACUAUUGCAUUUCAUCUUCUUUCUAGCUCCCCACCCUCCAAUCCUCUCUGCCAUAUACACACUUCAUUUAACUUAGCCAUGGAUAUAUUUGUCUUUCUUUUUCACGUUAACUUCCCAUCAGACUUGACAAAAUGCCAAAUUAGCUGUUCACUUUUGGUGGAUGAAGGCCAGGUACAGAUGUGUUAUGGCCAGCUAGGUUUGUGGUUUGUGGUUCACCUCUCUGCUGAAGGCCUGGAUUGUAGCCAUGUUCAUCUGCACCAGCCCCGGGGCCCAAGAAGAAUAACAUGGUUUUGUUGGGUCAAAAAGAUACCCAUGGAGAAAAAUCCAAAGGUAGCAAUGGCAGCUGCCAUCCCAGGUAGCCCCAGACUCAUGCUCAGAAGCCCUCACACCCAUCAUGAAAUCCUGGGCCAUGAGACUAGACUGCUAUAGAAAGAGUGUCAAACCAGGGAGGAGAAUCCACUAGAGUAAAUUUUCUUUAAGGAAAGAUAUUUAGAGUUCAAGAAAGAUAAAGACAUGAAGAAAACUAUGUGGGGUUCUGUAGUGGACCCACACAGCUCAGAAGUAGGACGCCAGUCCAAACCAAGACAUUAAAGACUUGUUGCAAAUUAUUGAAUUUUGCAUAAUCAUCUUAUGUAAUUUGCCUAAUGGUCCUUAGCAAGCCCAUUAGUCUUUUAACCAUAAAUUUCACGUCUGUUUUAAUUUCCAGAUUUCCAUUGGUAGUACUUAGAAAACUAUAACUGCAGGCCAGUGGGUCUUAACUGGUUUCCUGUGGCACUCUUGAGUUGCUAUAGACCCAUCGUGAAUGUAAAUGAAUAUUUUGAUGGAUGUGUACAAUUUGCUUUCUUACAAAUAAAAUGCAUACUCUUAUAGCAAUAUUACUUAAGCAGAAUAUACUAUAGAUAAUGGGACCCAUUUACAAGCAAGGGGAUCCAAUUUCUGCAAAUUAUAGGAAAGAGCAGAGUGUAGUGUUGCACCAGCAUCAGAUAAAACAUUUAUAGGAACAUUCAAGAAUGUUGUCUUCUAAGGACUCAAGAGCAUCAUCAAGGCAGUACUAAGUUUUCAAAGAGCAACGUAAUGCUUAAGGUCUACCCAUGGGAGUGAGGUGGUAAUUCUGGAUGCUUUUGUAGACACUCAGAAGCGUGUACCAGGGACUACAUUACUACUGUUUAUUACUUCUUUUUUUUUUUUUUUAAAGUUCUUAAUUGAUUCAACUGUGCCACCAAAAUCUCUGUCUGAAGGUGAACCAUCAGUAUGAAAUUGAAUCAUUGCCAUUUGGUUGUGAAAUUACGAACCUCGCCUUUCCUACCCACAGACUUCUUUCAUAGGUGUCUUGGUGUACCCCCACCUCCUCCUCCAGCCUCUGCCAAUAACUUUCUCACAAGUCUUACAGCCUCUUUGCAGAUAUCAUUUUCUCUUUUACCUCCCAGCUUUCAAGAGCUAAACUUGUCCUGCCUUGGUACUGCACCUGCCUCCUCUUACCAAGUGUCUUCCUGAGUUUGCACACAUUCCUUCUUGUUAGUACAUUUCCUGUUGUUAAGAAGCUGACAACCUCACCUUAUUGCUGCCGCACCCCAUUCCACAUUUAAUGACAUCCUCCACCCCUACCCCUCCCCAGCUCUGGUGAUGCUUUUUAGAGGGUGGUUCUCCAUGUUGGCUGUGAUUAACAUCACCUGGGGAAGUUUCACGUUUACUAUAACUUAUUUCCAGGGCCCACCCCCAGUAAUUUUGGUUAAAGUGCCCUGGGGGUGGGGCCCCAACCUUGGUAGUUUUUAAAUGCUUUCCCUGGGGAUGCAGCCAGCACUGAGAACCACUGGUGCAUAGGGUGUAAUACCUGUCUGUUGUAGGUAAUGAGAGCAAUUGUGGAAGGGGUAGCAGGGAGUUUUGAAAAAGGAUGAAAAGAGAUUAAAAAACAAACAACUCUUCCUCAUCCCUCUGUUUGCUUUCAGCUUCAGCUGAAGAGAAUGAGUUCUGCUAAGUGGCACCUAUGCCCACCUGGCUGGUGUGACUUCUUCCCCUUAGGCCUGUGUUCUCAUCAGUAAAUUCCUGACAGCCUUGUGCCCCCAGCAGGCCAGAAACCAUUCCAGGCAAGGCCUUUACUUAUCUCAUCAUGAGGCAGCCUACCAGGGGCCUGAUUUUCCUUUCUUAACUGGGCAUCCUACUUUGCAACCUCGUAUUUCCAUUUUUCCUUUUUGUAAGGCUCUGUAAACCAAAGCCAUGCACCCUCCCCGCUCAUCUGCUGUCAGCUCACUUGAAACUCACCAGCCCAAAGGACACACACAGCAGAACCAAUUAAAGUUCUCAAGUAGAGAUUGUUCACUUCACUUUUCACUUGCAAGAAAGAUGGAUGGCAGAGUCUUUGCUGGAAAACUAUUGUGUAGAACAUAAUUUUGCUGAAUUAAAGAGGGGAGGCCACUACCAAAAUUGAGCUGUCAUCUUUUUGUAGUUUUCUUUUAUUCUUAAUACAUCUAUGGGCCUCUAAAAUCCCUUUUUAUAUAUUAUCAAGUCCAGGAGUUGGGCAGAGAUUCAUUUGGGUAGCCUUUUUUAUAAAGUGAUCUUUGUGAAGUCUCUUCUCAAGACUUUCUGGGGGUCAGAAUGCAUGUUCAUUUUCCAGAGGGCCAUACGCAAGGACCAUUGGCUGUUCCCCACGGCUCUACAGUUUCUAAAGGAGCUGAGAACACUUACAACAUGAGUGCCUUACAGUACUCUCUGGACCUCAUUGCUUUAUUAUUAAGGAAUUAUUUCUUCCAAAUAUAGUAGUUUUAUUUUUAUUAGUAAGUAGGAAAAUUUAAGUGAGGUGAUUUUGGUGUUAAUAACAAGGAUUCAGAGCUGUUUUAAGGAAAUCCAAUGUGAAAUUUACGUGAAUAUCCAGUUGUACAAAAAAAUUAAGACAAAACGCUUCACUUAACAAACUUCUUCAUAAGAAUUAUUUAAAUGCCAGCCUUCUUUAAUGGAGUCCGUUUACAGAAAUUCUGUUUAUUCAUUCAUUUUCCCUGAGCACAGAUAUUGCACAAAGCAAAUACCACCCUGCUGUUGUCCUGUUGCAUGGUAAGAAAUGCAGCUUUUGUAUUUAUCAGCCUUACACAUAUAGUGUGAGAACCUUGCCAAGGCUGGCAGUGGUGCAGGCCAAUAAUUAAUUAAGGGGGCAUGCAGCAUACAUUUAUUGAGUACCUAGUAUGUAGCAGGCACAGGGAUAGGUAGUACAUAUAGAAGCAAACAGGCUAUCUACCCUUACUUCCUAGUGGAAAGAGACAAUCACAUAACCAAGGGAUUAUCAGUAGUAGACAUUUGGUUUUAGCAGAGAGUAAAAUAUAUAUACAUCGUUAGGAGUGACUGGGAGGCUAGGGAGGGUCCCCCUGAGGAAGAGACAUUUAAGCUGAAAUGUGACCAAAACAACCAGGGUUUGCAUGAAUUGAGACCACCCUGGACAGAGUAUAUGCAGGCAGUUGAAGGAGGCCAGAAGGGCAGAGAGUUGAGGUUGGGUGCCUGUACUCAGGAUCGGGAAGCAGCAUGGCCAGGUUUAUAUUUAGGAAGAUAACUCUGGUAGCAGCACAAAGGGUGAAUUGGAAUCCAAGACAGCAAUGCUGGGAACUCAAAACCAGGAUACUUGGUGAGAAUAGAACAGGCAGCAUGCUGACUUGAUGCUGAAAUGCUGGGCUCCUCUUUUGUCCUCUGUCCUCUGUCCAAACCCAGAUUGGACCUCACAGCCCCAUGAGUACACUAGACCUAAUGAACUUGUUAAAAUGCUUUUUUAAAAUGCCAACUUGUGUACCUGGUCCUCAUCUAAUGACGUGGAUUGGCAUCGAAGACUUCAUUAAAACUUCAAAUGACCUGAUGCAGGGAGUUCAUGGACCAAUCUUUGAGAAAUAUUGUGUCUAAAGACUGUACUUUCACUUUAAUAUUCCAUUUAAUUCUCAAAACAACCCUGUAAGAAAAACGUAUUUUUCCUAGCUUCCAGAUUAAGAAACAUGCCCAGUGUGAUUAAGCAUCUGGCUCAAGGUCACACAGCUGGUGCAUGUUAUGGCUGGCAAAGCAAUGUGCUUCUUUUCAUAGAGAGUCCUGCCUGUGUGAAAAUGGUAAGAACAACCCUGCAAAAUUCAGAACACCUUUGAGGGUUGUUUCAUGAGUGAACAUGGUCAAUCUCUCAGAUACAGGACUCAAUAUAUCCCAUCUUGGGAUAGAACCAGAGUGUUCAUUUUUGCUAGCUUUUCUCUUUUCUGAAGAAGUUUAAUUUUUUUUUCCCUCAAAGCUAGAAUUUUAAGUUCUAGGGGAAAAUAUAUAUAUAUUGCAAAGAAGAGCUUGGAUCUUAAUAUUGGUGUUUCUGGGCCUCUUUUUCCCAUAAAAGAAGUUGAAAGGUUUAAGGGGUAGCAUAAUUUUAUCACCCAUAGACCUAGAAACCCAACCAUUAGGCCUCACAGAAAAUUGUCAUGCUUUCAGUUGCCAUGAAUCAUUUAUUUCUUAAGUGGCUCUUGAACCAAGAGUUGCAAAAAUGAUGUUGAAGAUGUGGAGGAGGGUUGCUGAGUGAAAAGCACACUGAUAAUUAGAAAUCUUGCUUAAAAGCUGGCUUGAAAACACAUUUGCUUCAAUAAAUUACCUGCCUGCCCCCAUCUGAAUGUGUGAGGAAGGUUCUAGCUUAAUUUGCUCAUGUGGAUAGGGUAUUGAACAUAUUUAUCUGAAAGACUUAAUAUCAUAAUAAGUUUAGCCUGGCCUGACUUUUAGGACGAUGUCCCUCCUGGGGUAUAGGUAGAGAGGAAGAAGAUGAAAAACAAAAAAAGACAAGAAAACAUUUUCCUAUGGUGGCCCCCUGCUCCACCACACGCUCUCAGCUGGGGAGAACCGCAGUGAGCCCUACCGCAGCAUCCUCUAGAAUGUCAGCCCACACCCCACAGCAGACUGCAGGGUGUUAACUGCCUGUCUCUGGCAUGAACCCAGUUUGAAUGAGAUGCCAGGAAGUGAUGGAGGGGCUAUACCUCCCCCUGAAGCCUGGCCAUUACGUCCUGCAGAAUUGACCAGGGCAAGGCAGGCCGUUUGGUUUACAGACCACACCAUGAUUGUCACAGUGUAGAUUGCUGCUUUGAUUAUUUUGGAAUGUUGGAUGAACACUCCUUCCUGAGGUUAUUUUCAUCAGCAACGAUCAAAUUCAGUUGCUACUGCGUGUGGCUGAUCGUCCAGAGAGGGUGAUUUCUUGUCACAGGUUUCCCUAGGGGGAUAUUGUGCUGCUUGGUCUUGGUGGUCAGUCUCACAUCAUUUAUGGUGUAAGGUGGGCUCAGGGCCACAUCUGGGGGUAUGGCAUACAAGACAUGAUCAUGUUGUAAAGGCAACGUGUCUACCCCCUUGUCUGUGCCUACAUUUGUGUCUAAGUGAAAGAGGAACCUCAGAGACAAUCUUGAAAGGAAGACAGUUAACUGCAAUUUUAAGAAUGAUGGAUUUGCAUGAGGGAGAGGCUUUAGCUUUGUGAUAAAAUGCGAAAGCAUUUAUGUGUUGAUUACAUAGACUGUUCGUAAAGUCUGGAAACAUCUAUGUUCUAGAACAUAUUAUGUGAAGUAAAAUGAACAUACCAUUAAUUAUACAUGGGUCUUCAUUGGUUUCUAGACUUUCGGACCACCCUCAGACUUUUUAAAAUUAAUCAUGUUAGAUUAUCUCCCCAAUUCUAGCUGCAUCCUGGAUUCAUGUCUCACCCACUGAAGGUAGAUGCCUUACCUGGGGCAGAUUCAGGUAAGGCAUACAGUCAGUUCUGUUCUCUGUGCAGCUGGUUGUGAUGGUGCCAAGAAGGCUGUAUGCUGUCAGCAUACCAUUUGCUCUGUUUUGUUGUUGUUUUUAGUAUAUGUCUUCACUUAUUAAACAUUUAUUAAGGAGCAAGUAUUUUUAAGUGCAGUAAUAUGUAUCGUACAUUAAGGCCUCACAAUUGCUACUUUGUAGGAAAGAAAAUCUAGUUGAAGUGGUGGUGUGACUUGCCUAUAUCAUGCAGCUAAGAAGGUUUUGAGUUGAGAUUUAAAGAGAGAUCUGAUACAAGGCGUGUUUUGUGCUUUCUCUGUCAAUUCUCAUAUAAUUUCUCCUGUUAAAGCUCACUACCACAAGAAAUCGGCAUUAGUUUUGAGAUCAGUUAGGGAUUAAAAGUGAUUUAUUAAAUCAGACCCAUGUCCUUAUGACAUAGGUAAAGUGGUAUAUACCAUGAACUUGAGAAACAAUUUUCAUUAUUUUUUCUAUAUGAGGUGGAGAAAAGCAUACUGCUCAAUGAAGAACUUAAUUUUAAAAGUUGUAAUGCUGUUUCAUUUGUUGAAUUAGUUCCAUGACGAGGGAUACAAUUUUGGAUCAAGCUAAUGUUGCUGAAUCUGUAGAGGGACAUCAACAUUUGAUGUAACCUUUCAUGUUGAACUGUAAAAAAAGAAAACGGACUUCAUCUUAAUGUAUUUCACAUAGAUUUCCAUUACUUUUCACUGUGUUUUUGCCACUCUGUACAUUUUGCUUAUAAUAAAGGGUUGGUUAAAGGAAAAUAGAUGUAAUUUUUGGCACUUGUCUGCUCUAAUAUCGUGACUGACACUCAUAAUGUACAUCCAGUUCUCUUAAAUCCCAUAAAAAGCCAUUGGGAAGAAAAUUUUUGAGAUAAUAUAAAUAUAAUCUUACGUAAGACCUGUGUAGCCACUUCUUAUAGACAGCUUAGGAAAGAAAGAAGCCUUCAAAUAAUUACCAAAGUAGGAAGAAAACUAAAAACCUCUCGUAUUAAGGGUAAUAAUUGCAAAAUGACACCCACAUAGAAAAAGUCCCUUCCUUUCAUUUUCUUGAAAUAUAUUGAAACAAAAAGUUAACUAACAUCAUUUGGGUACCUUUUGAGAACUUUAAAAUAUAUUAUUUUAAAAUUGAUUUUCUUAAGGGUUAAAUACAUGGUUUUGAAGUUUUUCUUAAAGUAUUUUGAAAGUAUUUAAAUUGAUUUUAUGUAAACUUUUGCUACUAUUGGAUGCAGCCUUUUCAGCAUAGCAAAUGCAAUGUCCUUACUUAAUGAGGUUUCUAAUUUUUAACCUCAAAAUGAAAUGAAAAAUUUGUUCUAUUUCCAGGAACAUGGAGUAGACAUACUUUUCCCUGUUCUUCCCACUAAGUACAACUAAAAUUCCUAGACAUUGUUCAUAAAACAAACGUAAGAAGACUCUGAAAGGUAGAGGAAAGAUGGCAGAAUAUCUAUAGACCUCAAAACCCAAGCAACACACAAUAGUGAGUUACCUGGCUUUUCUUCUUUUUGAGUCGUAUUUCCCAGAGCUCACAUAUUCCCUUUUUUUUUUUUCUAAGAUGGAGUCUCGCUCUGUUGCCCAUGCUGGAGUGCAGUGGUGCCAUCUUGGCUCACUACAACCUCCACCUCCCAGGUUCAAGUGAUUCUCCUGCCUCGGCCUCCCAAGUAGCUGGGAUUACAGGCAUGCACCACCACGCCUGGCUAAUUUUUAUAUUUUCAGUAGAGAUGGGGUUUCACCAUGUUGGCCAGGCUGAUCUUGAACUCCUGACCUCAAGUGAUCUACCCGCCUCAGCCUCCCAAAGUGCUGGGAUCAUAGGUGUAAGCCACCACACCUGACUGAGAUCCCAUAUAUUCCUGAUGAAGAAGGCAGCAAGUGGAAAACACCAACAGGCACAUACAAAAACAAAUAAGUAAAAGAUGAAAAUCUGUUUUCUGAAACCAGAGGACUAGAAAAGGUAGAGCCUAGCAAAAUGGAAAACUUUUAGAUAAUAACUGUUGUACUCUAGCCAAGCCCCACAGAAAAAAAAAUGUGGCCUCACCCUACCAGCAAAAGCUGAUAGGGAAGCCUAAACUUCCACCCUUGCCAGCUCUAAAUUGAGAGCUGGGGUGUCCCAAGGCACCCCAGCCCUCGCCACUGGGUAGUGUCACAGAAAACUGAGUAGGGAGCCAAGGCUUUUAUUUCUGCUGCGUAGUAACAAGAGCCUCCACCUCAACCCCAUGUAAGUAGAAACCAUAUGCGGAACCUGGGUUUCUACCCUCCCCAACUCCUAACAGUAAUGAGGAGCCCUUUUCCUCUCCAACUGGGGUGGUGUUAGUGGACAUCAUGUGGGAACCAGAAACACUGUUUCUCCCAGCCAGGAAGUAUUGUUGGAGGCCCGAUGGAGAGCCAAAACUCCCACUCCUAACUAGCAGUAAGAAUGCAUCCCCCUCAGGUAUCAGGGGAGGUGUAGUAGGGAACCUGAUUCUACCCCAGUAAUCAGGAUGAACCAGCAAUAAUAACACAGUCUCCCCAUUCCCUUCUGGGAGUGGUAACAGAGGAAGGCAACUAAAAUAGAAAGUUUAAGUAAGAUCCAAAGUCUCAUAACAUAAUACCCAAAAUGUCCAGGUUUCAAUGAAAAAAAAAAUCACUUGUGAUACCAAAAACCAGGAAGAUCUCACACUGAAUGAAGAAAAAAAAAAGCAGUCAACAGAGGCCAGCACCAAAAUGACAGGGAUGUUAGAAUUGUCUGCUAAGGAUUUUAAAACAGCCAUCAUAAAAAUGCAUCACUGAGGAAUUCUAAACAUGCUGGAUGCAAAUGAAAAAAUAGAAACCUCAGGAAAUAAAUAAGAAAUAUAAUGAAGAACCUAGGGGGCAUCUUAGAACAGAAAAAUACAGUAACCCAAAUAAAAAUCUCAGUGGAUGGGCUGGACAACAGAAUGCAGGGGACAGGGGAAAGAAUCAGUAAAGAGAGAACCAUCAAAAUUAUUUUGUCUCAACACUAGAGAGAAAAUAGAAUAGAGAGCCUCAAGGACCUGUGGAACUACACUUGACAUUUACCAUUUGUGUCAUUAGAGACCCAUAAGAAGCAUAGGAAGAGGGAGGGGCUGGAAAAGUACUUGAGCAAUCAUAGCUGAAGACUUGCCACAUUUAACAGAAGACUGAAACCUACAGAUACAAGGAGUUGAGUGUAGUAGGCCAAAUAAUGGCUCCCCCGCCAAUGAUGUUCAUGUCUUGAUUCCCAGAACUAGGGAAUCAGGUUCCUUUUUUCUUUUUAUUUUUUAAUGUAGUAAAAGGGAUUUUGCAGAGGUAAUUAAUUUCAGGAUUUUUUUUUCUUUUCUUUUUUUUUUUUUUUUUUUUUGAGACAGAGUCUCACUCUGUUGCCCAGGCUGGAGCACAGUGGCACAGUCUCGGCUCACUGCAACCUCUGCCUGCUAGGUUCAAGUAAUUCUCAUGCCUCAGCCUCCCGAGUAGCUGGGACUACAGGUGUGUGCCACCAUGCCUGGCUGAUUUUUGUAUUUUUAGUAGAGAUGGGGUUUCGCUGUGUUGGCCAGGCUGGUCUUGAACUCCUGACCUCAGGUGUUCUGCCUGCCUCGGCCUCCCAAAGUGCUGGGAUUACAGGCGUGAGCCACCAUACCCGGCCAAGGAUUUUGAGAUACAGCAAUAUCACUCCUCAGCAUUUAAUCCCAGAGAAAUAAAGUCACAUUCUCACAAAAACCUGUGUAUUAAUGCUUAUAGCAACCUUAUUUGUAAUAGUCAAAACUGGAAAUAACCCAAAUAUCCUUUAAUGGAUGAGUGGCUGAACAAACCGGUACAUCCAUAUCGUGGAAUACUACUCCACAAUAAAACAAAGGAGCUAUUGAUAUAUGCAGCAGCUAGUGUGCAUCUCCAGAGAGCCAUGCUGUGUGAAUAAGCCCAAUCCCAAAUGGCUACAUGUAACAUGACUCCAUUUAUAUAACAUUCUUUAAAUGAUAAAGUCGUACAAAUAGAGAUGAGAUUCACGAUUGCUAGGAGUUAAGGAUGUGGUAGGGACAGGAGGGAAGUGGGUGGGGCUACAGAAGGGCAACAUGAGUAAUACUUGGUGAUGGAAAUGUUCUAUAUCUUCCUUCUAUCAGUGUGUUUACCUUAGUUGUAAUGUUGUAAUAUAGUGUUGCAAGAAGUUACCAGUGAGGGAAACUGAGCAGUGGGUACAUGAGAUCCCUCUUUAUUAUAAGUAACUGCUUGUGAAUCUAUAACUAUCUAAAAUUUUAAAAUUUAAUUUAAAAAAUAACUUUUAAAAAUUUCUUGUAGCUACAUCAAUUUGAAAACACAAUGCUAUAUCAUAUAUAAAGAACUUUGCAUGUCCAAGUUCAGAAAGAUGUUAGUACGAAGUUGCCUCUUCUAAAGUCUGUUUUUUUUUUUAAUUUGUUUGGAGAUUGGGAAGGAAGGCAAGGGAUUCUGUUUUAUCAAUCAUAUAUGUUAAAAAAUAGAUAAUAUUUGUUAACUCCUAAACACCGUGUGAGGUCAGCAUUAUUGUAAAGAAGAACACUGAGACGCAGGGAGGUGGAAUGAUUUGCCCUGAUGAGUAGUGAGGCCACAUUUGGACUGGACAGUCUGGUCCCAAAGCCUGCAUCCUUUCUUACUGACUAUACUCUUUGGCCUAUCUGCAUAGGCUAUUAGUAUCCAAGUAUCUUUCCGCAGCAGGACACUCACCUCAGAAGUUUUAAGCACUUUUCCUAGGUCACAGAGUCAUAGCUGUGAGACUGAAAUUCAAGACUUUUCCUAUCAAAAUCCCAUCCUACUCCCACCUGGGAGAAGCCAUAUUCCAAAUGGCCCUCAGACCUGAUCCUCAAGCAUAUUUUGUUUGCUCACUUAGUGCUGGGCAGUAGAUUAUUCUUUUUAAAUUUACAUUAGCAGUAUAUAUUUAAACAUUGUGAGAUAUGUAAAAAUCCAGGCUUCUAGCUUCUCAGGAAAAAUAAGAAAAUCUGCCAACACUGGGUGUACAUUCUCAAAUUCUCUCAAAGGAGUUAGAUAUAGGAUGUUUAGGGACUGCCUCUUACAGCCUCUUUAGAUGAGGUUGUUUGCCUCAGUCCUUACCACUACUUACCCAGAGACCACAACCAACCAUCAGCUGGUUUUUAUUGUGCAACACUGUUGUUUUUCUUACAGUAGAGGAAAUGCCUCUACCCACCUAGCUACCAAAUCAUGGCUUUUAUGUUUUACCUUUUAUCUUAAUAAUUUGGGUGGUUGUAUUCUUCCUGAUUAUAAACUACUUAAAGUUCUAUUUCUGAAAAUCUCCAUUAUUAGUGGAUUUGCAGUUGUUAAACUUAAGACCCCCAUAGAAUUGAAGGUGCUGAAAUCACUAGUCCAUCUACGAAGGCUAGUCACUAAAACGAAAUAGGCAUACAUGAACUAGAAUAUAUCUCCUUCAAUACUUCUUAAAUUAGAAAAUUAUGAGUAUUGCGCAGUCACUGUGUUCGUCAUUACAAUUGCUUUAACAUUCCUUUGUAAAGACUUUCUAGUAGUUUUGCGGAGAUUCAAUGAGGUGCUUAUAAAUUGAUUUUGUGCCAGGUGCAGUGGCUCAUGCCUGUAAUCCCAGCACUUUGGGAGGCCUUGAUGGGAGGAUCACUUGAGCCCAGGAGUUUGAGACAAGCCUGGGCAAGAUGGCAAAACUCAACCUCUACAAAAAAUUUUAAAAAUUAUCCGGGCAUGGGGGUAUGUGCCUUUAGUCCCAGCUACUCAGGAGGCUGAGGUGGGAGAAUCACUUGAAUCUGGGAGGUUGAGGCUAUAGUGAGCCAUGGUCGUGCCACUGUACUCCAGCCUGAGCAACAGAGCGAGACCCUGUCUCAAAAAAAUAAAUAAAUAAAUGAAAUAAAUUGAUUUUGCUUCAUGGCAUGCGAUACGCAUAAUAAUAAUAAUAAUAAGUAUUUCUUCUGUGUCUGGCUUUCUACUGAAGUAUUUUCAGUUCUACAAUUCAAGGCCCCUCCACCCCUAUUGGUCUUUCUCUUAAGGGGCCCAACUCUGAGUGUCUCUCCUGAGUCUCAUAUGCUCAGUCUGAAAUAGUUGACCAAGUAGGAAAUGGAAGUAAAGAAUUUCACGGAAGGGGAAUUUGCCAUGAGGGAAGGGUUAAUAAGUUAUUCCUGUUGAUCGCCUUUGUAAUGCCUAGCACAUUCUCGUUACAGAGUAGACAUCCAGAAGUGAAAUGAUUAUGUUUGAUGCUGAACUCCUAAGUAAUUCAAUAUUGUCUGAGGAUAAUAGUCCUGCAAAUUAUAUUACAGUCAGAAGUGUUUUUGUUUUUGUUUUUUUCCAGUCGAGGAGUAGAUGACUGGAGGCUGCCUUGUUUGCGUGAGUGGUGUUGGGAUGACCUUCCAGGCUGGGCAUGUGAUUCCUGAAGAAGUGGCUACUUGUUUGGCUCCUAUAUCAAUGCAGAAAUUAGUGUUUGAGCUGAUAGGAAGUAAGGGGGGGAAAUCAAGGAGUGGAAAGGCUGCUUGGGAUGGAAUCUGUAGACUCUUUCUGUCUGACCUCUGGUUGCUAAUCUAUGUUAUUGUUACUGGAAGGGGAGGCCUGCAAAGGUUGAGUCCUGGCAAGGAUAUCACCAGAGCAGGAGAUCAGUGACUUCUUAGCUUAUAAUUCCACUGUAGGUGAAACUCUAGCAUUUGCAGGCAAGAUGGAAGAUAAGGAAGUGGGUGAAGGGGUGAAAAAUGAAAUAAAUAUUGAAUAAAGCGCCUGUACUCUGGAACCAGAUUGUGCGUUUUUAGUUUCUGCCUCACUCUGUCAUACUAUUGUGUAAGCUUGAGCAAAUAAGUUAUCUCUGAAUGCUUCAGUUUCCUCAUGUGUAAAAUGGGAAUAAUAAUAGUAUUUACCUCAUCGUGUAAACAGCCAGUAAGUAGCAGCAUCUCUGCACUGGACAAUUUUUCUUUUGUCAAUUGCUCUUUUUAUUCGGUACCUACAGUGUCAUCUAAAUAGCCUGUCCCUUAGUGUAUGGAGUCAGGAGACUAAGAAGAAAUUUAGGGAAAAUAAGGAAGGAUAAAGGAAUAAUAAGCAAGGAUGAAGGAUUGCCUGCAUUUGAGACCCUUGUCAAUGUGUGUUUUCUCCAAAGAAAAUGUGUCUCUUUUCCAAAGAAACAUAGAUGUGUCUCUUUGGAGAACUUGUUUCCAACCUUAGAUGAUUUUUCAGAUUCAGUCUGUGUGCUAAACUCAAAUCUUCUCAUUUUCUAAGUACAUCUGUUCAUGACUUAUAAUAUGUUAGGAAGGUAUUUUGCCCUGGUGAAGAAGGACUUAGUUCUUAUUCCUACUUAACUAAGGGAUAGAGAAGAAAAACCUUCAAAUUACAAUGAAAUUGAUUGACCUCAAUUCUUUUUAGAUAUUUGUCUACAAAAUGUCUUUAGUAAUAGGUUUUAAUACUUUUGCAGUUGAUUUUACUAAACAGAUUAAAAAUUUAAGCCCACUUAACCUCAAUAAACAAGUAUAUGAAGUCACAUACAACUAAGUACUUCAAACCCAGAAACUCUGGCACUGAAGGAGAUAAAGUAGCAGACACCUUCUGUGUAUUUUCCUACUUCUGUACCUCAAGACAUUUGCUGUGUACAUUUAUAACAAUGGCCAUGUCGGAAAUAAUAUUUUUGGGUUUAUGGAUUUUUAUUGAUCUAUUUCAUUUACGUGGGUUUGAUCCCAAAUGAUGGGAUGAUGUUCUCUUAUGAAGACCAUGCCUUGAGGGAAAGGAGAGUGCUUUUAAGUAAGCCUGUUCCCUUCUGGCUCUCUUUGAUAGGGUGGUCUCUCCCAGGGUUUAUUUAGGAAAUGAUGGAACACAGGUCAGUCUGUCCUUGUCUCUAACCAAUCUAAACAUUUUGCUUUCAGCAAAAUUUACAUAUUAUUUUCAAACCUUUACUCCACAUCUUGCAUUAUUGAUUUGAUUAAUCUCUGCUGUUUUUAAGGCAUAUCUUCUUCAAGACAGCAUUUUUCUUUUAUAUCCAACAAAUUCCUUUCAGAUUUCUAAAUGCGAAAAAAAAACUUAGUUGUGGACAAAAGUACAGCCAUUCUCUUUACACCUGAAGAAAUUAAUGUUUUUUCGAUAAAAGUCACCAUAUGUUAGGAGGGUGACAAUUGGUAUUCAAAUGUGAGUGAGGAAAAGAAUAAAGACUGAGGCAAACAAAUAUUACCAUUAUUGCAGUGUUCCCUGCAAUCUGUGGGUUGUUAUUUAUUUACAGUUUUGUUCCUGUAGGCCCACAGAAGAGAAAUGCAAGGAGGAGUACUCCUGAAGUAGAAGAGGCUGUAGAAGGUUGGAAUAGAGAGCAACAAAUCCCAGAAAACACGAGAUUUUUCUCCUAUUUCAGCAGUUGGCCACAACUUCAUUGCUGGGAAAAGACUUCCAUACAUCAGGACUCUUCCGUUUGAAAGUAACUAGUUGAUAUUUAAAAAAAGAAGAAGAAGAAAAGGAAGUGAAAAGAGAAAAAAAAGAAUGCAGAAGUGAGGAUUAUUUCUUCAUGAAGAAUAAGGUUUGUUCCAGUUUUAAAAGCCUGUGACUUCUCUGUGAAAACAUUGCAGAUGAUUAGCUCAGCUACCAGGAGCCACACAGUUUUCUUAGAAAUUGUGCCAUUGAGGACACCAAGGGGGCCAGGGAGGACACAGCUCCAGUUAGAGGCUGGGGCCUUGAGCGCCUCCCCCCAAGAGCAGCUGGUGCUCUGCCAGGUCUGUGGCUCCCAGGAUGCCCAGAUCCCUUGCCAGAGGUUUGGGAGAAGCCUUAAAGGUGCUGUCUCUUCGGAUCUCUGCUGUUUCCUCUCCACUGAUAGCUACAUUGGGAGCCUCUUCAGAGGAGGCUUCUAGGAAUUAGAAGGGAAAGCAUAUAAAUGCCAUUCACUACAGUACCUGUUCACUGCUGGUCACAGUUGUUCUCCUUUGCCUCAUCAGCCUCAGGCAUGGAGAUAACCUGGUGGCAUGUCAGUGUCUUCGAGUUUUUCCCAUUAAGCUCCAAGAGCAUUGAUUGCUAUUCACUUCAUGAAUGGAUGUCUUGAGAAGAUCGUAAGAACUACUUUUGAAGGACCGAGGCUGCCGUCUCUGCUUCAGUAGAAACCCGAGGUGCCUGACAUGAAAAGCACACUAGAGGACCUAUUUGAAGAAGAGAGAGUUAGCUGUUUGGAAUCUAACCGUUUAUGUUAAGUGAAACACUGGGCCGCAAAGACUUAUGAAAUAUAAGACAAAACUUUGUCCAGGCAGGGAGAUGGGACACAAUCUCACAACAGCUUUUAAGAUCAUCUAAUAAAUAGGUCAUUGGAUUCACUCUGGAACUGAUAUCCUCUCCAAGACCAAAAGCUUGAUUCUUCAAGUUUAAAAAGAAGAAGAAAAAGAAAUCUGCACAUCCACAGCAAAACUAGAAAGUCAGGGAGAACUACCAUCAGUGGAGAAGGAUAUUUAAGAAUUCCCAGAAGCAGAAUGCGUGAAGGGACAACUCGGGGCUAGAUCUGCAUGUCGUCCAGGUGACACUGUUCACGCUGCACCAAAGUCUCCUUCUAAUAAGAAAUUUUCAGAACUGAAUCACAGCUUACCUUACCAAAAAGCCAAGAAAGAAGAGAGAACUCUCACCACAACAUUUCAAAGGGAAUACAUUGCCAGAACUUGGAAUACUCUACUGGACAAACAUUUCCUCCAAGGAGGCACCCUGGUUUGCUGCGAAGCCACCCCUGCCGUCUUGAUGUCUGUGCUCAGGGAUGGCUGAAAACAGUCACAGCUUUAUCACUGAAGCAAACGAAAAUGACACAGCUCUCUGCCUCCAUGUCACCACCUUUGAAGGACUGACUGAUUCCCUCGGCUGGUGCCAGUGCCUGCUCCUGCCAUGGGGCCCGCGGGGAGCCUGCUGGGCAGCGGACAGAUGCAGAUCACCCUGUGGGGAAGUCUGGCUGCUGUCGCCAUUUUCUUCGUCAUCACCUUCCUCAUCUUCCUGUGCUCUAGUUGUGACAGGGAAAAGAAGCCGCGACAGCAUAGUGGGGACCAUGAGAACCUGAUGAACGUGCCUUCAGACAAGGAGAUGUUCAGCCGUUCAGUUACUAGCCUGGCAACAGAUGCUCCUGCCAGCAGUGAGCAGAAUGGGGCACUCACCAAUGGGGACAUUCUUUCAGAGGACAGUACUCUGACCUGCAUGCAGCAUUACGAGGAAGUCCAGACAUCGGCCUCGGAUCUGCUGGAUUCCCAGGACAGCACAGGGAAACCAAAAUGUCAUCAGAGUCGGGAGCUGCCCAGAAUCCCUCCCGAGAGCGCAGUGGAUACCAUGCUCACGGCGAGAAGUGUGGACGGGGACCAGGGGCUGGGGAUGGAAGGGCCCUAUGAAGUGCUCAAGGACAGCUCCUCCCAAGAAAACAUGGUGGAGGACUGCUUGUAUGAAACUGUGAAAGAGAUCAAGGAGGUGGCUGCAGCUGCACACCUGGAGAAAGGCCACAGUGGCAAGGCAAAAUCUACUUCUGCCUCGAAAGAGCUCCCAGGGCCCCAGACUGAAGGCAAAGCUGAGUUUGCUGAAUAUGCCUCGGUGGACAGAAACAAAAAAUGUCGUCAAAGUGUUAAUGUAGAGAGUAUCCUUGGAAAUUCAUGUGAUCCAGAAGAGGAGGCCCCACCACCUGUCCCUGUUAAGCUUCUGGACGAGAAUGAAAACCUUCAGGAGAAGGAAGGGGGAGAGGCGGAAGAGAGUGCCACAGACACGACCAGUGAAACUAACAAGAGAUUUAGCUCAUUGUCAUACAAGUCUCGGGAAGAAGACCCCACUCUCACAGAAGAAGAGAUCUCAGCUAUGUACUCAUCAGUAAAUAAACCUGGACAGUUAGUGAAUAAAUCGGGGCAGUCGCUUACAGUUCCGGAGUCCACCUACACCUCCAUUCAAGGGGACCCACAGAGGUCACCCUCCUCCUGUAAUGAUCUCUAUGCUACUGUUAAAGACUUCGAAAAAACUCCAAACAGCACACUUCCACCAGCAGGGAGGCCCAGCGAGGAGCCAGAGCCUGAUUAUGAAGCGAUACAGACUCUCAACAGAGAGGAAGAAAAGGCCACCCUGGGGACCAAUGGCCACCACGGUCUCGUCCCAAAGGAGAACGACUACGAGAGCAUAAGUGACUUGCAGCAAGGCAGAGAUAUUACCAGGCUCUAGCAACCCAGAAGACAACCCUGGGUAGCCUGUGAUCAGUGUCUGGAGACGUUUCUUCUGUGGAAGAGAAGAAGUGACACAAACCUAUACUUCAUAUGCUGCUUUAGUCACCUGAAGAUGGUUGGAGAGGCCCUGUCGACUGUUCUCCCAGUUGUUCAGUUUCUGAGACAGAGAGGUACGGACUAGGCUGCACCUGAGUGUGCCCCUGCCUGCCAGAUGGACAGGUACACCCAAGCACAUCUCCCUGCUGCACCCUCACCACCCACAAAAGAUCCCAGCUGUCAGUGGUCUCAUCUCAUUAGUGAGGAAAGCCAAGCUGUAUGGAAAAGCUGCACUCACCAAGGACCACAAUGCCCCCGGCCUAAAGUACUGCCAUUCAGAAAAGCAGGUUUUUCUUCCUCUCUUUCCUUUUCUCUGUCUGCUACUGACUUUAAGGCUUUUUCCCCCUUGAAAUGUCCAGAUUCCUGUGGUUCAUCCCAAGGAAAUUUUCACACAAAGCUUGGCCUUUGCCCUCAAUAUAGGUGUUUUAGGAUGGUGACAAACCAUGGCUGCUGCUUUCUGCCCAGCUCGCCAGUCCUCCCCAAAGAGUUGCGCAUCAGCACCUGGGGAUCUGGACCCUGCGGGUGAAGGGAUGGGGAGGGACGUCCCUGGAGUCUCUUCUGUCUUUGUUCCUUCUUAUUUUGGCAUUCGAUAUCAGCAGCCUCUCCCCAAAGUACUUGAAGUCAGUUUUAGAUGCUUUAUUUUAUUUUUCUAGUCAAAAACGUGUUUCCCCCAGUGUUUGAAAACUCGUCCGAAUCUUUUCAGUAUUUUCCAUGAGUAUUGUGGUACUUCUAGACUUGUUUAAGCCCAGAACUCAUUCCUUCAAAACAGAGAGCCUUAAUCUUUAUGUUGGGACACAGACCACAUAUUUGGACGGCAGCCAUGCAUCCAUCGCUGAAGGGCUGUGGACAUGAAUGUGUAUUUCCCAUGGUCUCCGCUGCCCACACCAACAGUGUGGCAUCUCAUAAGUUAACUGCUACCCUAAGGUAAUCUAAGAUUAAAAUGUAAACAUUUAUUUUUGUUAUGUAAGUUUAUAAGAUGUUUUAUGUUCAAUGCCUAAUUUCUCAAAAGUGCCAGAAAAAAAUGUAUAUUAGCUAUUUUGAUUUUAUGUACAAUGAUUUAUACUCUCCUUUUGAAAAGAUACCAUAAAGCACAUAAGCUAGAUCACUACAAGGAGCUGUUAUCUUUUUUCUAAUCAAGUGUUUAAAACACUGAUGGUUUUUAAAGACUCACCUUUUUAAAUGGUACUUGGAGCUCCUGAUUCAAAUUACCUAGACCCCCUAGAGAAAUAAAUGGAAUAUACAUAAAUAAUCAUUUUCAGUGGUUUAUGGUGGGCAAUAUUGCAAUAUUUGAAAUGGUAAAAAUGGAAAGAAGAACAAAAUAUGAUGAGAGGUGGCUGUGAAUUAUAAACCUCAUAAAAGUGUCAUAAUUCCAUUAAGGUUUAAUUAUAUUUUUUCAGAAAACAGUGAUGAAUUCUGUAGUCCAGUGCUUGCCAAUGCAAAUUGCCUAUUGGAAUCUUCUUCCUAUAUUUUACAAACAUCAGUGGCUGAAAUAGCUCAGAGUAAGAGCUCAGCCUGGUUUGAAUUUAAUCAUCUCUUUAGAUCUUAUAAGGCCAGCAUUAGGAAACUUGUUCACUUUUCAUUUUCAAAGGAGCCUAGUUGAAGUGCUAUUAUGAGUGUGGGCUAUGGAAAGACAGCUUUUCCUACACUGAUAAAGAAAAAAAAUGAGGAAAUUAUUUCAUCCCCUUGUGACAUCUGUGACUUUUUGGAUUUAAUAAUCUUGCUGUUUUUCCUCUUUAUGACAAAGAAUAUAAUUGGGAGGAUGAAGUGUCUUAAAAAUUGUAGAGACCAGCUCACUGGAAUGUUUUUCCAUCCCUGUAUUCAUGGCUUGACUUUGUGACUGCUCUACACUGCAUGUCUGACAUUGCAGAGUGAGCUAUGUUGAGGUAAACUGGUUGGUUGUCAUUAUUUUGCAAUCAGCCUGGUCUCUCCCAUGAAGAUGUCGUGUGCAUAAGCACAAUCAUCACUGAUUAGAAGAUCACAGCAGAAUACCCUUGGAUUAGAGAGAAGUUCGUACCUUGCAUUUCUCUGAAUUCUAGUCUCUCAUAAGCACUGCUUUGCUGGAUGAUUUUCACUGCUUUGUGUUAAUGACUUUGAGCGAUCUCUCACAUGAUGGGGUUCUUUAGUACAUGGUAACAGCCAUGUCAUCUUACACACCUAGCAUUGUGAAUGCUGUAGUGACAUCCUUUAUAGGCACCUUACAGCUCAAAACUUUUGUUUCAUUUCAUGCCUUACUUAUCAAAAAGGCAGGAAAGUAGGUAUGAUCUCUAAAGUAAAAAAAAAAAAAAAAAAAAAACUUUUUAUAGAAAGCUCAUAAAUAAUCAUGUCAUUUUGCAAUUUUGUUACCAAAAUUUCCCCCAAGAGUUUUCAAAUAUUAGUUCUGCAAUGUGGCUAUGAAAUAUGCACUGAAAUAUACCUUUUAAUUUGAGAACCAGUGGUUAGAAUAAGCUGUGAUAUAAAGUAUUUUCAGUGUACUUUUAAAGGAACUAUAAGGCCCUCCAGCAUAAACGCUAAAAGAAUAGAUGGUAGCACAGGCCAUGAGGGCUGGGGGAGAGAAGCAGAGUGAACCUUAGAAAGAUGGCUCAGCUAUUUGGAGCACUGGAUAUUUUACUGAAGUUAUUUACUGAGGCACCAUCACUGUUUUGACUGUACAGUAUAGUUUUUCAUAAAUUUCAUCACAUUUACUUUGUUCAGAAUCUGGGCUUGAAUCUUUGAGUUGGACAAAAGCCUAUGGUUUCUUUUAAAAAGUUUCAUCUUGAGCUAAUGCUACAGUUUAAAUAAAAUGUAUGAAAGGUAGUUAUCAAAAACAAUUUGUAUAUUUAAAAUUCUAUUUUGACAUCCAUUUUUUACAGCGAAUUAUAGCAGGUUAUGUGAAAUUUAAAAAUAAAUUUUAGGAAAUUUUUUUAUCUUGUAAGUAAGAAUUAUAAAUCUAUCUCAGUUAAAAGUAGGAUCUUUGUUUUUAUUCAGAUAUUUUGAAAGUUUAGAAGCAUUUUGUAUGCUACUUUGGUAUUUCUUAAGUAUAGUCAGCAGGAAAGGGUAACCUGUUUUAUGCAAAAUUUUUUUAAUUUGUCAAAUGUUUUUAGUGUGUCUACUUUCUGAAAUAGUCUCAAUAUCCUGUCUGUAUCCUAGGCAGAUAACUACACAAGAACAAAACGCUAUAUAGAAAAGAAAAUAUUUGAGGAAAUCUUAAAUUCCAUAAGAAAGUAAUUCUUGCAAGAAUGUUGGCUACAUAUUUUUUUUUCUGUCCUGAAUAAAUUACAUCAUUAGGUCUGUUGAAGCUUUUGAAGCUACCACUAUUCUUUCUGGGAUAAAGGCUAAUUACUGAUUUAUCUGCCCUCAAAAUCCCAGAGUUAAUUCUAAUUGAGUACUAAAUUAACAGUAAGUAGUUAACACAGAGAACUAAAAUUUAACCGCAUUAUAUCACUGUAUAUAUUUCUCAUGAUUUUUGCUAAUUAGAGCAUUUACUUAACCAGUAAUAAACUACACACACACACACACACACACACACGUAUACGUGUGUGUGUGUAUAUACUUGGCUCUGACACAACUCUGGUGCUUAAUUAGGAUAUGUUCUAUUAUGUAUUUUGAAUGUUUAUCCUGCUAGUGUGAUGAACUUUUGUUGGAAAAGCAGAAUUAGAAGGAACAGUUUUUCAAUCAGUUUCAUUUGGUAAUUACAGGAAAACCUUGAGUUGCUCUAAUUUAAUUUUUCCAAUUAAUACAUUUAGACUUUAAAUUGCAUCCGUAAUUCUCUUGGCUGAAAAACAGUGGUAUUUUAAGACAGUUUUGUUAUACAUGUGACUUACUUUUGACUCAGCCUGAGAGGAGGAAAUGUAAAGAGAUAAGAGAUUUGGCCCAAAGCAGCAAGAGACUAGUAACCUUGAGCCAGGACGAAGCCAAGACAACGUGACUCCCAAGUAGCAGGAGCAGAGGUCGGUCACCUGUGGCAUUCUGUUUCAUUCCCUUUUAAAAUUAUGAGACUUUAUAGGCAGUGUAAAACAUCAGCAGGCAGCGAUGUGAUAGGAUGUGCGAAAAAGCUGGUCUGAUACCAUGGCUAUAAUUACAGAGCUUUAGUUCAAUUAGGAUUUUGUAAAUGAGCAAAUGACCUUUUUUUCCAGUGCCCCUUGUAAUAGUUAAUAUGAGUCCAUGCAAUCUUGUGAUGCCAUUCUCCUGAAGGUGUUGAUUUCUGGUACCCAGCCAGCUUAGCUUUGGCUGCUGGAAGCACAGUAGGUACUGAUGAUUACUUCCUGGAAAUCUUGACAGGCUUAUUGUACUGUGUAAUGGGGAAAAGUUAAAGUAUAAUGUUUGGUGUUAAUAAAUGACUGAUGUGAAAAUAGGAACAUGUGUCUUUAAUAUCAAAUAUGGCUUUAUUUGCAGUGAAAUCUAAAUUCCUUAUUCUACAGUAGUAUUUUCUUGCCCUGUGUUGUAUAUUUUCCUAAAUACAUUUUUCCUGACAGUGGCUUUAGGCCAGUUGAACACACUUAGACUGAAAGUGUUUAACUUAAAGAGAUCAGUCCAGAAACCAUGAUAAAUUAGAAUCUUUAUCUGGAAUUACCAAAUUAAAAUUUAAAAUCAUGGUCCAGAAGAGAACAAACAUUCAUGGUUUUUUUUAUCCUACUGCUCAUUUUUAGGUCUGUGUUUACAUCUAGUCUCUACUAUUUGUGAAGUAUGUCAUUAUUUUUUUCAAGUUCUUCUUUGACUUAACUGAAAAAUAAUAUUCCAAAUUCUUAAUGUAACAUGAAAAGAGAAAUACAAUUUUUGCUUAAAAGACAUUUUUUAAAAAGCGUUCAAUUCAGUAAUCAUUUCUGUUAAUACAGGAAGUUUUUUUGGCUUGCCAGUUAUAUACUGUGGGUAUUUUUUAAAAUGUGCUACCCUUGGGUUGUCUCAUAUCACCUUGCGUAAUCAUGUAUUACAAAGGUUGAUAAUUGUCAUUUCUCAGAUGUCUGUAUGUUACAUUGGCAGCAGUAAAAUGUUUUAAUGUUGUUACCUUUUAAAUAAUUGUGUUGUAUUAACAUGCCUCAUAUUUUCUGGGGAAACUUGAAAUAUAUCUAAACAAAAAAGGUCUGUUAUAAAUAGGAAUUGGCAUUUCAUUGUUAAUGUUUUUUCCUCAUAAAAAUAGUUACACCAAAAGUGACAUAUUGUCUAUUACAUGGGCCCAAUCAGUAUUAAAGUACUCCCCUUACUCAAAAAUAUUAAAAAAUAAUUCAUGACACUUAGUAGCAUUUUCAUUGAUUGUUUCAAAAGAUCUUCAUAAUGGUCAAAUUGUCCAAUUCACAAAAGAGUGAGAAAGUUGUUUUCAGUACUGGGAAUUUUUAAACCUUAGUUUUAAGACCAAAAAUAUCUCUUAUUAGCUUGAACAUUUUGUGAUUACUUUUCCCUCCCCGGAUCUAGUCCUUUUAAGGAGUAAGUCUAAAGAAUGAGGCCAUGAAGUCACUAUUUCCUCCCACCUCAGUUUGUCUCCUGGUACUUAGCUGGCCUAUCGCUUUGUGUGGCAAUACCCCUGGGUCGCUUCCCCACUCAGCCUUCUGUAUCUGCUGUUCACAGGACAUGCCAUUAUGUCUUUCCAGUACGGAUCACAGUGCUGCCAUAUCACAGACCCUGCCAGCCGGCACAGAACCAUGCCUCGUCACAGCUCUGCCCAACUCACAGGCUGCCAAGAUGAGGCCACAGGUCCACCUAGGGCGGCAGAUGCUGGUGCUAUUUGUCACGACUUUUGCCAAAACAUGUACACUGUUGCUCACAUCUUUCGUAAGAAUGGUUGACACUAAGGGGCCAUGGAAAAGCACUUUUAAAAAAUUAUGUGGUGGAAUCAAACUCACAGAGGCAGAAAUGUUAGUGCCGUGCUCUAACCAAGUAAGCUUAGUGUUCCCCACAGUGAUCUGUAUCUGGCCUGAGUCUCCUCAAGCAGCAACCCCCACUGUCCAGCAUGUGGAAGGUAGAUCCUUAUGACAACACCAGACCCAUAGUUACCAGGAAAGAAAAAGGAAGCUGAGUGUUGUGAAGGGGAAGAAAUCCUUUUUAUAAGAAGUAAUCAUUUUUAGGCCGGGUGCAGUGGCUCAUGCCUGUAAUCCCAGCACUUUGGGAGGCUGAGACAGGUGGAUCACUUGAGGUCAGGAGUUUGAGACCUGCCUGGCCAACAUGAUGAAACCCUGUCUCUACUAAAAAUGCAAAAAAAAUUAGCCAGGCAUGGUGGCAUGUGCCUGUAGUCCCAACUACUCAGGAGGCUGAGGCAGGAGAAUCACUUGAACCUGGGAGGCAGAGGUUGCAAUGAGCUGAGAUCGCAACACUGCACUCCAGCCUGGGCGACAGAGCAAGACUCCAUCUCAAAAACAAAAACAAAAAAAAAACCUUUUUAAAGUAAAUUGAGUGUAAAAUGUUUUCACCAUGAAGCCAUUGCACCCUCUCCCCCAGGAAACAGUGCCUAAGGAUGAUGUCAAGUUACAGCCAGUUUGCUCUGAUCCCCCAGGACCUAAGAAAACUGUGAGUGCUUCAGCAUGCAAAGGUAGAGCUACCAGAUAAGGAGAAUAACUUGGCCAUUUAUAGCAAACUGCCUGACUUUGGAGUGAGAAACCAAGCACCUUCUAGGUCCUAGGAUAGGUGAAUUGGAGGUGCAGCUGCUGAAGUUCCCAUUUUCUACAUACUUCAGGAGCCAGGGUGUUUCAUUUGGUUUUGUAAAACUUUGCUGUAAGUCAUCACAGUUAAUUCUUUGAAUGGACAUUUUAGAGUGUAACUUUUUUUCAAAAUUAGCAGAACAGAUAUCUCUGCUCAUUCUCUUUAUACAUUUAGUUUUUUAAAGUUCCCCUAGUAUACCUGUUAGGCACUCUAAAUAGGACACAGUUAAAGCUAAAAGAAGGACCAGUUGCUCCCUAGAGCCUACAGUUCAGAACUAUCUUGUUGUCAUGUCCUGGUUUGGUUUGGUUUGUUUUUAACUCAACAAGUUGGAAACCAUGAGUUUAAAGCAAACUAUUUCCUUUUCUUAAGCUUAAAGAGAAUUUUUUUUUUAAUCUUUAGCUCCUCAUUUAGGUAGUGAAGGCUUCCCUGAAAGACAGCAGUGCCCUUCUCUGGAAGAAGAGGCUGGGACCAAAAGCCUGAGUCUAUGGGUUGAGGAUUUUGAGCAUUCCUUUGACAAGCUUCUAUGUAUUUUUAAUAUAAGACUCAUAAAUGAACCUGAUGUGGUGUUCAUGACCCAUCCCUUAAGCAUGCUUGCUUUUUUUAACUUUACUUUUUGAGUAUAGUACUUGUCUUGUUUUUCCUGGAGCCAUGCUAGGAUUUAAUUCCUAUGUGCCACUACCCGCCCAUGUCCUGGAAGAUGGCCAUGCCUGCAGCAAUGCUCAUGUCUUGAGGAGAAGCAAUGUGAAAAGCAUCAGGAAAGCUGAACCUUACGUUCAAGUCAGCAAACAUUUGUGAGCAUUCUAGUAUGCUUGCGACCUUGACACUUUUUAAAAAUUAUCUUUUUAUUUGCUUCGAGUAUCAACCGUAUAGUUGACUCUAGUGGGGCGAAGGGAGCAGAGAUGAGAGCAAAAUUCAGACUUGCUGCCCCUGUGUGUCUCAGUUCUCAUGUCUCUCUGAGAAAUGUGUUGGCCCAAUUCCCUAUCUGCCACUCUGAGUCUCUUGAGUAAAUGUGUGUAAAUGAGAAAAAUUAUCUCAAAGAUUUAACUUAUUAUUUAGAUAUUUUCUUCUUUUUAAACUCAGGAAUAAACCUGGUUUGUAGAUAAUAUAAUAUGGCUACUAGAGCUAUAAUUGAGUAGGUGACUAGAAGCAUUUUUUCAAAUAUAUUUCUUGUAAAGACAUCUACUUUGUUUUAACUAGGAAAAGAAACUCCUCAUAUUAAAAUAAACAUUUCCAUAAGCACUUUCUAGAAGAGUGUAGCAUCCAUCUACCAUCCAUCCCAGAAUGUUUGUAUCUUGCUCAUAGUAUUUCAAAAAUUUUUAUGGGUGAAAAAAAUGCACUUUUUUAUUUAUUGGAAAAGUGUAGAGUUAUUGAAUUAAAUUCUCAAGUGGGACAAUUUAGUGUAAAGGGAAACAUGGGUUUUGGAGACAAGAGCACAGGGCUGUGGUCCCUGUUCCAGCAUUGACUUUACUAUGUGACCUCGAGCAAAUGAUUUAACUUCUCUGUGCCUCAGUUUCUCCAUAUACAAAAUGGGGAUAAUGAUACUAACCAUUGCCUACCUCAUAGAGAUGUUAUGGGGACAAACGAAAUAAUAGAGAUAAGCACGAAUGCUUUCAACUCUUCGGAAGAAAGGUGCUAUAUAAAUUGAAGUUGUGUUUUUAAUGAUCCAAUUAUUAAUUAUGUUUAGGGUUUAAAUAACAAUACUGUUAGUCAUGUUAAGAAUAAGUUUUGUUUUGAUGCAUAUUUCCACUUCUCUUCUGUGGCCAGAUCUUGAUCAUUCAACCAGUAAUGGUACCUGAGGAACUGAAAUGGGUAUUUGUUUUCGUAUGUUUCUGCCAGUAGUAUUUCAAUUGAAUAUCCAGAAAAGACUGGAGUUUAACUUGUAAUAUCUUAUAGUUUACAUGUAAUAAAACUUAUUCAAGCUAUAUAUAAAAGUAUGAUUACAUGUAAAUAGCAGGUAUGUUGUAAUUAAAGGCACUUAUCAAAUUGUCUUUGUUCUUUUUUAAUUGUAAUAAAAGUCAGUUUUACAUAAA